GUUACGGCGCUCAGGCGUCUCGACGCGCGCGAUUUAAAACCAGCUCAGGAGACGCCAAGGAAAGAUGGGACCUCCCGGCCCAGCACUGCCAGCCACAAUGAAUAACUCUUCUUCAGAGACGCGAGGACACCCCCACAGUGCCUCCUCUCCUUCAGAGCGUGUGUUCCCGAUGCCCCUGCCCAGGAAGGCGCCUCUCAAUAUUCCUGGCACCCCAGUCCUCGAAGACUUUCCUCAGAAUGACGAUGAGAAGGAGCGGCUGCAGCGGAGGCGCUCGAGGGUCUUUGAUCUGCAGUUCAGCACUGACUCACCUCGCUUAUUGGCCUCCCCCUCCAGCAGGAGUAUUGACAUUUCAGCUACUAUCCCCAAGUUUACAAACACGCAGAUUACGGAACAUUACUCCACCUGUAUCAAACUGUCCACUGAAAAUAAAAUCACUACCAAGAAUGCUUUUGGUUUGCACUUGAUUGAUUUUAUGUCAGAGAUUCUUAAACAGAAAGACACCGAACCAACCAACUUUAAAGUGGCUGCGGGUACUCUGGAUGCCAGCACCAAGAUCUAUGCUGUGCGCGUGGAUGCCGUCCAUGCCGAUGUAUACAGAGUCCUUGGGGGGCUGGGCAAAGAUGCACCGUCUUUGGAAGAAGUAGAAGGCCAUGUUGCUGAUGGAAGUGCUACUGAAAUGGGAACAACCAAAAAGGCUGUAAAGCCAAAGAAGAAGCACUUACACAGAACUAUUGAGCAGAACAUAAACAACCUCAAUGUCUCCGAAGCAGAUCGGAAGUGUGAGAUUGAUCCCAUGUUUCAGAAGACAGCAGCCUCAUUUGAUGAGUGCAGCACAGCAGGGGUGUUUCUGUCCACUCUCCACUGCCAGGACUACAGAAGUGAACUGCUGUUUCCCUCUGAUGUCCAGACUCUCUCCACGGGAGAACCUCUCGAGUUGCCAGAGUUAGGUUGUGUAGAAAUGACAGAUUUAAAAGCGCCCUUGCAGCAGUGUGCAGAAGAUCGCCAGAUCUGCCCUUCCCUGGCCGGGUUCCAGUUUACACAGUGGGACAGUGAAACACAUAAUGAGUCUGUGUCGGCCCUGGUAGACAAGUUUAAGAAGAAUGACCAGGUAUUUGACAUCAAUGCUGAAGUUGACGAGAGUGACUGUGGAGACUUCCCCGAUGGGUCCCUGGGGGAUGACUUUGAUGCCAACGAUGAACCUGACCACACCGCAGUUGGGGAUCAUGAAGAGUUCAGGAGCUGGAAGGAGCCCUGCCAGGUUCAGAGCUGCCAGGAAGAAAUGAUUUCCCUUGGGGAUGGAGACAUCAGGACCAUGUGCCCCCUUCUGUCUAUGAAACCUGGAGAAUAUUCUUAUUUCAGUCCUCGGACCAUGUCGAUGUGGGCUGGCCCGGAUCACUGGCGCUUUAGGCCUCGACGCAAACAAGAUGCUCCUUCCCAAUCAGAAAACAAAAAGAAGAGUACAAAAAAAGAUUUUGAAAUUGACUUUGAAGAUGAUAUUGACUUUGAUGUAUAUUUUAGAAAAACAAAGGCUGCUACUAUUCUGACCAAGUCCACUUUGGAGAACCAGAAUUGGAGAGCUACCACCCUUCCUACAGAUUUCAACUACAAUGUUGACACUCUGGUCCAGCUUCACCUCAAACCAGGCACCAGGUUACUUAAGAUGGCCCAGGGCCAUAGGGUAGAGACUGAGCAUUAUGAAGAAAUUGAAGACUAUGAUUACAACAACCCUAACGACACCUCCAACUUUUGCCCUGGAUUACAGGCUGCUGACAGUGAUGAUGAAGAUUUGGAUGACUUAUUUGUGGGACCUGUUGGGAACUCUGACCUCUCACCUUAUCCUUGCCAUCCACCUAAGACAGCACAACAGAAUGGUGACACUCCAGAAGCCCAAGGAUUAGACAUCACAACAUAUGGGGAGUCAAACUUGGUAGCUGAGCCUCAGAAGGUAAAUAAAAUUGAAAUUCACUAUGCCAAGACUGCCAAAAAGAUGGACAUGAAGAAACUGAAGCAGAGCAUGUGGAGUCUGCUGACAGCGCUCUCCGGAAAGGAGGCAGAUGCAGAGGCAAACCACAGGGAAGCUGGAAAAGAAGCGGCCCUGGCAGAAGUGGCUGACGAGAAGAUGCUUAGCGGGCUCACGAAGGACCUGCAGAGGAGCCUGCCCCCUGUCAUGGCUCAGAACCUCUCCAUACCUCUGGCUUUUGCCUGUCUCCUACAUUUAGCCAAUGAAAAGGUAGGUAAUUAAGAAUCUAAAACUGGAAGGAACAGAGGACCUCUCUGAUGUUCUUGUGAGGCAAGGAGAUUGAGUUCACUAUGGAGAAGUCAGCAGCAGGAGGCCCAUCCCUUACUCAGUUGCCGGGACAUCCCCAGUCUCGGGGGAAGAAGAUGCCAUGGGCUUAUACCCAGGCUGUAGCCAACUACCAACGUGCCUGUUUGUUUGUUGCUCUUUCCUUCUCUCCAUCAUAGUCUGGGUGCCAGCGCCCUGAAGCUCCGUGCUCAACUGAUUAAACUUUACUGCCCUAUGGUGACCAUCUAGGAGAGGGGAGGGCAGAGGGGGUGAGGGUACUAUUCUGGAUUGAGAAAACCUAUAUCCAUUCUUUAUAUCAAUGUAUAGUUUUAGUCUCCUAAAUUGAUCUGUUAUUUUCCAAACUAUUCUCUUGUAGAAAAUUUUCCAGUGGGCACUUAAUGGUGCCCUUGAAGAACUUCCUAAUCCAUGUACAUAAAAUACAUCAUAUGUACACUUAUAAAUGUAUAUAGAAUGCUCAAAAAUAAAAUUCUUAAUAAUAGAACUGGCAAAAUAUUUGAGUGUCCACUAGAUGAGUAUCAGACCUAGUCCUUACCCUUAGGGGGAUGCAGUCCUGGUUGUUAUCCAGGAUACACACCUGUCAGUAUAAGGCAGAAGAUGCCUAAGGGCCAAGAUGGUUUGCCUCGGAGGAGAAUGGAAGAGAGAGAUUGCUGACUGGACAUUCAGAUGCAAGACUGGGUCCUGCUUAAAUCCCAGGAUUCUGCUGGAGGGAGCUGAUAGUGAUACUUGUCCCUUCUGUACAUUGCUUCAUGUAGCCUUCUCAGCAUCCCUAGGAGAAACUUACUAUUGUGACUCUCAUGUUGGAGGAGGAAACGGACACCCAAGGUAGAGGAACUUGCAAAAGGGCAGCCGGCAAACUGUCAGGGGUGGCCUGAGCCUGGCAAUCUGCCUCCAGAGUCUGCUCUCGGCCAUUGUGCUAUGUGCUACCUGGAUAGGUCAUACAGGCUCAGCAGUGGGUGGAGAGCAGUGCUCAGAUUUGUCCAUCUCCACAGAAUGCAGCACACACACAAAUGUACAAGUUCUUCCCCUAACCUCAGAGGAAUAGGGGAAUUAACUUUGCUUGCAAUUUGGAACAAUAUUAUAGAUGUUGAUCCAAGUAGUUCUGUUACUGGCUGGUCCUGGAUCUCUGCCAGAACACCCGUCAUCAUUGACUGGCUAAAUAGAGAUCUUGGAUAUAGGCCAGAAGCAGUGAAGUAUAUAAUUGGAAAUUGCUCCUGAUAAUAACUUCCUUCUUAGCCAAAAACCACACAAAACAAAAAUAAUCCCCUCCCCACAGGAAUAUGCUUUCCAAAUUGUGUCCAAAACAUUACCUGCUCUGUUAUAUUGAGAAGGUUAGAGACUUCAGAGCAUGCUUAGAAAAAGCAGUGGUGCCACAGGUGAGACUCCACACUCUGUCUUGCUGGGGCUGAAGCCUCCAUCACUUUCCCAGGCCAGGUUAGUGCUGGGCUUCUUGCUUUCCUUCUAUUCCUGAGAGUAGAACUGGCUAAGCCCAUUCCUUCCCUCAGUCAGCCCCACUUCUCUAUAGUGGGUUCUGGGGGUGGGGGGCUGAAUUACCAGUAAAACUAGAAAGAUUGGGACCAAGUGCAGUGGCCCACACCUGUAAAUCCUAGCGCUUUGAAAGGAAGAGGCAGGAGGAUUGCUUGAAGUCAGGAGUUCAAGACCAGCCUGGGCAAAAUAGAACCCCAUCUUUAAAAAAAAAGUUUAAAAAUUAGCCAGGUACGGAGGUGUGUGCCUGUAAUCCCAGCUACUCAGAAGGCUGAGGUGGGAUAAUCACUUGAGCCCAGGAGUUUGAGGCUGCAGUGAGCUGUGAUCACACUACUGCAUUCCAGCCAGGACAACAGAGUGAGAUCCUAUCUCUUAAACAAAAAAAAAAACUGGCGAGUUCAAUACCAACUUCUACAAUGAAAUCCCCUUCCCCCCACAACCCUGCUUCUCCUAAGUUUCCCUCAUUACAUGGUUGCUGUGGGCUAUGUGUGCUGUGGUCUGAAUGUUUGUGUCUAAAAUUCACAUGUUGGUAUUAAGAGAUAGGGCCUUUGGGAGGUGAUUAGGUUAUGAGGGCAGAUCCCUCGUGAAUGGGAUUAGUGCUCUUAUAAAAGAGGCCUGAGGAAGCUUGUUCGUUCCUCUUGCCCUUCUGCCAUGUAAGGAUGCAAUGAGAAGGCACCAUCUGUGAGCAAGGAGCCCCUCACCAGACAGCAAAUCUGCCGGCGUCUUGAUCUUGGACUUCUCAGCCUCUAGAACUGUGAACAAUAAAUCUAUUGUUUAUAAAUUAAGCAGUCUAAGUCAUUUUGUUAUAGCAGACAAAUUGACUAAGACAGUGGGUAUGCAAGAUAAGUUUAUUUUAUAUAAAAUACUUUGGGAAGUAGGUGUUCUAGGACUGGUGUGACAGUUCCAUGAAAUUAUGAGAGACCGGGGAUCCUUCCAGCUCAUCCUUCUGUUUCAGUGUGGCUGCUGGAAUCCAGCCAUCACAUCCAUAGUCUAAGCAGCAGGACGAAGGACUGGGGGAAAAGAGAACUGCUGCUCCCUGUUAAAUCAGUUUCCUGGGGGUCGAUAUGAAUAUUUGCCACCUCAGGGUGCCACAAAGGUCCCCACCAGCAAGAAGGCUCCCACCAGAUAUGGACUCAACCUGGGACUUUUCAGCCUCCAUAACUGUAAUAAAUUCCUUUGUCAGUUACCCAGUUUCAGGUAUUCUGUUAUAGGUAACAGAAAACAAACUAAUACAAGUGGUAAUGUGUCCAGCUAAAAAUUUGGGUUCUGUUAAGGUUAAAAGAAAAUUUGAGGUAGCCAGCAGUAUCUGCCUCAGAUGCUGAGAAGCCUCCUGAGAUAAGAGCGUAUACCAUGUCCAUAACUGAAGUUUUAACAUUCUCUGCCAAACAGAACCAGAAUUUAAGGGCAGGAGAAUUUGCAAGAUAGAAUUUGCAAUUUGCAAGAGGGAAUUGCAAUUUGCAAGAGAGGGGCAAUUUGCAAUUUGCAAGAGAGGGCAAUUUGCAAGAGAGAAUUGUGGGGCCCUGAGAGAGAAUACAUCCAAAGGAAGAGGGAACCAGGCAUUACAAAUUGAAUUGAACAAGGACAGAUAUCUGAAGGGGGUUUGUAGUUCCCAGUAAAGUAUGGUACAGCUAGGUGCACUUCCCUGGCCAGACCACCCUACAGUGUAUGAUCCCCCUGGGGAGCAAAAGGCUGCAGGUAACACUUUGGUGCCCUAGAAAUUCUGCUGUGGUGCAACUAUAGUGGAUCACAGGCAGAGUGGGGCAUUGUUCCCCUUCUUAGCACAGGAUACUGGGUCAUUUCAACACCACAAGGAUUUGCAGCAUCUGCGGCAACGAGUUUGGUGUCCUGGAGCAAGGAAAGGAACCGUUCAUGGUGGCUGAAGCCAAGCUGCUCAGCACUGAGGCAGCAAGCCAUGAUCUAGGUCUUCGAGUAGAAUUCUCAGUUUUGGUUCAUUUAAAAAUGUUUUUUGGGGGAAUUGGGGAUCAUUUAUGGGUACCAAAAGAAAAAAAAAUGAAUAAGAUCUACUAUUUGAUAGCACAAUAGGGUGACUAUAGUCAAUAAUAACAAUUGUAUAUUUUAAAAUAAAGAAUGUAAUUGAAAAGAGUAAAUGCCUGAGGGGAUGGAUACCCCAUUCUCUGUGAUGUGCUUAUUUCACAUUGCAUGCCUGUAUCAAAAUAUCUCAUGUACCCCAUAAAUAUAUGCACCUACUAUGUACCCACAACUAUUUAAAAAAUAAUAAAAUUUUAAAAAAUUGUC